GCAGUAGAGCCGCGUACGGCCCGGGUCAGCGCCCGCCCGCCCGCGCUCCUCCCGGCCGCUCCUCCCGCCCCGCCCGGCCCGGCGCCGACUCUGCGGCCGCCCGACGAGCCCCUCGCGGCACUGCCCCGGCCCCGGCCCCGGCCCCGGCCCCCUCCCGCCGCACCGCCCCCGGCCCGGCCCUCCGCCCUCCGCACUCCCGCCUCCCUCCCUCCGCCCGCUCCCGCGCCCUCCUCCCUCCCUCCUCCCCAGCUGUCCCGUUCGCGUCAUGCCGAGCCUCCCGGCCCCGCCGGCCCCGCUGCUGCUCCUCGGGCUGCUGCUGCUCGGCUCCCGGCCGGCCCGCGGCGCCGGCCCAGAGCCCCCCGUGCUGCCCAUCCGUUCUGAGAAGGAGCCGCUGCCCGUUCGGGGAGCGGCAGGCUGCACCUUCGGCGGGAAGGUCUAUGCCUUGGACGAGACGUGGCACCCGGACCUAGGGGAGCCAUUCGGGGUGAUGCGCUGCGUGCUGUGCGCCUGCGAGGCGCCUCAGUGGGGUCGCCGUACCAGGGGCCCUGGCAGGGUCAGCUGCAAGAACAUCAAACCAGAGUGCCCAACCCCGGCCUGUGGGCAGCCGCGCCAGCUGCCGGGACACUGCUGCCAGACCUGCCCCCAGGAGCGCAGCAGUUCGGAGCGGCAGCCGAGCGGCCUGUCCUUCGAGUAUCCGCGGGACCCGGAGCAUCGCAGUUAUAGCGACCGCGGGGAGCCAGGCGCUGAGGAGCGGGCCCGUGGUGACGGCCACACGGACUUCGUGGCGCUGCUGACAGGGCCGAGGUCGCAGGCGGUGGCACGAGCCCGAGUCUCGCUGCUGCGCUCUAGCCUCCGCUUCUCUAUCUCCUACAGGCGGCUGGACCGCCCUACCAGGAUCCGCUUCUCAGACUCCAAUGGCAGUGUCCUGUUUGAGCACCCUGCAGCCCCCACCCAAGAUGGCCUGGUCUGUGGGGUGUGGCGGGCAGUGCCUCGGUUGUCUCUGCGGCUCCUUAGGGCAGAACAGCUGCAUGUGGCACUUGUGACACUCACUCACCCUUCAGGGGAGGUCUGGGGGCCUCUCAUCCGGCACCGGGCCCUGGCUGCAGAGACCUUCAGUGCCAUCCUGACUCUAGAAGGCCCCCCACAGCAGGGCGUAGGGGGCAUCACCCUGCUCACUCUCAGUGACACAGAGGACUCCUUGCAUUUUUUGCUGCUCUUCCGAGGGCUGCUGGAACCCAGGAGUGGGGGUAAGUGGGAUGGGGGCAAAACACGUGAGAAGGUUAGGGAGAGCACCUGUCUCAGAAAGGCCCACAUGUGCGGCCUUGCAGGACUAACCCAGGUUCCCUUGAGGCUCCAGAUUCUACACCAGGGGCAGCUACUGCGAGAACUUCAGGCCAAUGUCUCAGCCCAGGAACCAGGCUUUGCUGAGGUGCUGCCCAACCUGACAGUCCAGGAGAUGGACUGGCUGGUGCUGGGGGAGCUGCAGAUGGCCCUGGAGUGGGCAGGCAGGCCAGGGCUGCGCAUCAGUGGACACAUUGCUGCCAGGAAGAGCUGCGACGUCCUGCAAAGUGUCCUUUGUGGGGCUGAUGCCCUGAUCCCAGUCCAGACGGGUGCUGCCGGCUCAGCCAGCCUCACGCUGCUAGGAAAUGGCUCCCUGAUCUAUCAGGUGCAAGUGGUAGGGACAAGCAGUGAGGUGGUGGCCAUGACACUGGAGACCAAGCCUCAGCGGAGGGAUCAGCGCACUGUCCUGUGCCACAUGGCUGGACUCCAGCCAGGAGGACACACGGCCGUGGGUAUCUGCCCUGGGCUGGGUGCCCGAGGGGCUCAUAUGCUGCUGCAGAAUGAGCUCUUCCUGAACGUGGGCACCAAGGACUUCCCAGACGGAGAGCUUCGGGGGCACGUGGCUGCCCUGCCCUACUGUGGGCAUAGCGCCCGCCAUGACACGCUGCCCGUGCCCCUAGCAGGAGCCCUGGUGCUACCCCCUGUGAAGAGCCAAGCAGCAGGGCACGCCUGGCUUUCCUUGGAUACCCACUGUCACCUGCACUAUGAAGUGCUGCUGGCUGGGCUUGGUGGCUCAGAACAAGGCACUGUCACUGCCCACCUCCUUGGGCCUCCUGGAACGCCAGGGCCUCGGCGGCUGCUGAAGGGAUUCUAUGGCUCAGAGGCCCAGGGUGUGGUGAAGGACCUGGAGCCGGAACUGCUGCGGCACCUGGCAAAAGGCAUGGCCUCCCUGAUGAUCACCACCAAGGGUAGCCCCAGAGGGGAGCUCCGAGGGCAGGUGCACAUAGCCAACCAAUGUGAGGUUGGCGGACUGCGCCUGGAGGCGGCCGGGGCCGAGGGGGUGCGGGCGCUGGGGGCUCCGGAUACAGCCUCUGCUGCGCCGCCUGUGGUGCCUGGUCUCCCGGCCCUAGCGCCCGCCAAACCUGGUGGUCCUGGGCGGCCCCGAGACCCCAACACAUGCUUCUUCGAGGGGCAGCAGCGCCCCCACGGGGCUCGCUGGGCGCCCAACUACGACCCGCUCUGCUCACUCUGCACCUGCCAGAGACGAACGGUGAUCUGUGACCCGGUGGUGUGCCCACCGCCCAGCUGCCCACACCCGGUGCAGGCUCCCGACCAGUGCUGCCCUGUUUGCCCUGAGAAACAAGAUGUCAGAGACUUGCCAGGGCUGCCAAGGAGCCGGGACCCAGGAGAGGGCUGCUAUUUUGAUGGUGACCGGAGCUGGCGGGCAGCGGGUACGCGGUGGCACCCCGUUGUGCCCCCCUUUGGCUUAAUUAAGUGUGCUGUCUGCACCUGCAAGGGGGGCACUGGAGAGGUGCACUGUGAGAAGGUGCAGUGUCCCCGGCUGGCCUGUGCCCAGCCUGUGCGUGUCAACCCCACCGACUGCUGCAAACAGUGUCCAGUGGGGUCGGGGGCCCACCCCCAGCUGGGGGACCCCAUGCAGGCUGAUGGGCCCCGGGGCUGCCGUUUUGCUGGGCAGUGGUUCCCAGAGAGUCAGAGCUGGCACCCCUCAGUGCCCCCUUUUGGAGAGAUGAGCUGUAUCACCUGCAGAUGUGGGGCAGGGGUGCCUCACUGUGAGCGGGAUGACUGUUCACUGCCACUGUCCUGUGGCUCGGGGAAGGAGAGUCGAUGCUGUUCCCGCUGCACGGCCCACCGGCGGCCAGCCCCAGAGACCAGAACUGAUCCAGAGCUGGAGAAAGAAGCCGAAGGCUCUUAGGGAGCAGCCAGAGGGCCAAGUGACCAAGAGGAUGGGGCCUGAGCUGGGGAAGGGGUGGCAUCGAGGACCUUCUUGCAUUCUCCUGUGGGAAGCCCAGUGCCUUUGCUCCUCUGUCCUGCCUCUACUCCCACCCCCACUACCUCUGGGAACCACAGCUCCACAAGGGGGAGAGGCAGCUGGGCCAGACCGAGGUCACAGCCACUCCAAGUCCUGCCCUGCCACCCUCGGCCUCUGUCCUGGAAGCCCCACCCCUUUCCUCCUGUACAUAAUGUCACUGGCUUGUUGGGAUUUUUAAUUUAUCUUCACUCAGCACCAAGGGCCCCCGACACUCCACUCCUGCUGCCCCUGAGCUGAGCAGAGUCAUUAUUGGAGAGUUUUGUAUUUAUUAAAACAUUUCUUUUUCAGUCUUUGGGCAUGAGGUUGGCUCUUUGUGGCCAGGAACCUGAGUGGGGCCUGGUGGAGAAGGGGCAGAGAGUAGGAGGUGAGAGAGAGGAGCUCUGACACUUGGGGAGCUGAAAGAGACCUGGAGAGGCAGAGGAUAGCGUGGCAGUUGGCUGGCAUGCCUGGGUUCCGCAGAGGGGCUGGGGAUGGUUCUUGAGAUGGUCUAGAGACUCAAGAAUUUAGGGAAGUAGAAGCAGGAUUUUGACUCAAGUUUAGUUUCCCACAUCGCUGGCCUGUUUGCUGACUUCAUGUUUGAAGUUGCUCCAGAGAGAGAAUCAAAGGUGUCACCAGCCCCUCUCUCCCUCCUUCCCUUCCCUUCCCUUUCUUUCCCUCCCCUCCCCUCCCCUCCCCUCCCCUCCCCUCCCCUCCCCUUCCCUUCACUCUCCCUUCCCUCUCCCUUCCCUUCCCUUCUCCUUCGUUCACAGCAAUGGGGUCUUGCUAUGUUGCCCAGGCUGGUCUUGAACUCCUGGCCUCAAGUGAUCCUCCUGCCUUGGCCUUCCAAAGUGUUGGGAUUACAGGCAUGAGCCACCACACCCAGCCCAGCCUCUACCUUCUUUGUCUAAAGUGAGGCAAACACUUUUCUGUUUUUUUCCUGGAAACUCGUGUUCUGGACCAGUUCUGGGGCAAACUGGGGUCAGAGUGGAUUGGAAUCAGCUCUGAUCCAGCUUUUGGCUGUGCUUACCUUGAGACCAAAUCAUGUAGAGAAUAAGACAAGACCCUCCUGCCCUGUUACCCUCUUCUCUCUCCCCUCCCUCAUUCCUACCAUCAAGACCCAGGCAUUUUGACAAGCUCUAGGAAAUGAGGGUAUCAGAACAGAAAUCUAACAAAUGUAUGUAGCUGCAGAUCCAUCUUUCAUAUAAACAAUGUGGAGUCAAA